AGGCAAUUGGGGACAAUCAGGAUAAUUGUUCUCUUCUUCAUCACAGGACUACUUCAAAUAAUCCUUUCCUCUUUCUCCUAGCCAGCUAGGUUUACAGUGAGUACAAACCUGUUCAGACAUUGUCCUGAUACUUGUGGAAUAUGUGCUUGUUCAUUUCUUUUCCAGAGUGUGAAAGCUUUGAAAGUCAUUUGAUGUUUAUGCUUUGGACAGUGACAUAUAAAAUUGGGUCAGGUAGAUCUAGUUCAAAUAUUGACUGCUGUGUGACAUUAGAGCAAUUCAAUUUAGCAUCAAAUCAAGGUAAAAUAAUACCUAUCUUAGAGUUGUUGAAUUAACUGCAAACUGUAUACAUGAGUCAUUUGGUGUAAUGUCUGGCCCACAGUAAGUGUUCAAUAAAUGUUUGUCAUCAUCAUCAUUUUCACUUUGAUAUACCUGAAGGUAUUUUUCUCUGGAGAGGUAUCUGAAACAAAACUUUUUUCAAUUCACUCUCACUUCCCAUCAUUCCCCUCCCUCCCUCCCUCCCUUCCUUCCCUCCUUCCCUUCCUCUCGCUCUGUCAACCAGGCUGGAGUGCAGUGGUGCGAUCAUAGCUCACUGCCACCUUGAUUUCCUGGGAGCAAAUGAUCCUCCUCCUGAGUAGCUGGAAUGACAAGCCACCAUUCCUGGCCCACCAUUCUUGUGACAUCAUCACAUGGUCUGGUCUAUGAUGAAAUGCCUCCAACGACAGAGAACUCACUAUCUCUAGGGCAGAAUUUCUCAACCAUGGGACUGUUGACAUUUUACAUGGGUCACUGUUUGUUCUCUGCACUGUGGGAUGUUUAGUGGCAUCUCUGGCUACAGAGACAAAAUCAUCUCUGGUUGAGAACCACUGCUCUAGAGACAGCCUAUCCUAUUUUUAUUAAAGUUUUGACCAUUAGAAAAUUCUUUCUUACAUUGAGUGGAAGUCUACUUAAUUUCUUCUACUCACUUCUGCCUUUUGGAGAAAUGUGGAACAGGCUGAAUCCCUCUUCCACGUAACAUCCUUUCAAAUAUGUGAAAAUAGUCAUCAAGUAUUCUCAGUCUUUUUGAUUUGAAACAUCUCCAGUUCAUUAGCUAUUCCUUACAUGGCAUGGUUUCAUGUCAGUUUACCACAUUGGUGGCUUUCCUCUUUUUAAAAAAAUUUCAUUUUAAACUGUAGUGCUUUGAAUUGAAUUCUGUGCUCCAGACAUGGCUUGAUACGUGAGAAAUAGAGUUGUAUCUCUUGUUCUAGAUAUAACACUUUUCUUCUGUGAGUUAAGGGAAGAAUAUCACCUUCCUUCUUCUACAUAAUUUUAUUAAUAUUAGCUAUAUCCUUUUGUGACCACAUCAUACAUUGAACAUAAAGUUGAAUAAAAUCCCUGCAUCUAUCUAAGCUAUGUCUUUUCAUCCUGUUUGUAUGCAUUAGUUUUGGGGUCCAACCAUGGGAGCUUAUGUUUGUCUUGUUAAAUUUCUUUUUAUUGAAUUUAACUAACUGCAACUUUUAAAGAUAUUUUGGAAUCCUAGUUCUUGGUUUAAUUGGCAGUUUCUAGCCUAAAAGAACAUGUAUGUGAUGAUGCUAUGCACUGAGAUUGGAAAUACAAGAGAAAGAAGUCACUCUCUCUGUCUCUCUCUUUCUCUGUCUCUCUCUCUGUCUCUCCCUCCCUCUCUCUCUGUCUCUCUCCCUCUCUCCCUCUCUCCCUCUCUCUCUCCCUCUGUGUGUGUGUGUGUGUGUGUGUGUGUGUGUGUGUGUGCAUGUGAUUGAAAAGAGAUUGAGUAUGGAAGCCUGGGUAAUACCAAUAUUAAGAGGCAGCUGGGCAGAAAGGAAGUAAGAAAGGAGACCAAGAAGUGGUGGUCAAAAAGUUGGGAUGAAAAUAAUAGGAGUAUCUUGUAAUGCUGGAGUGACUCUGUGUUAAGUACUGUGGUAGAUACUUGAAUAAAAAAUGAAUAGGACAUGGUCCCUGCUUUCUGCCCCUGUUUUUGUUUAAUUGUUCAGUUUAUGGAACUGCCUAGUCAGUCAUUCCUGAAGACUUGGAAGUCAUCCUUUAUUUCUCCCUCAUACCCUUGCCUCUUUGGGUUACCAAGCUCCAUUGAUUAAAAAAAUUUUUUUGAAGUGUAACAAAAAGGUGCAGAAGCAUCAAGCUCAAUUAUUUUUAAAGUUUUACAAAGUGAACACCCUGUAAUCACUACUACCCAGAUCAAGAUACUCAUUUUCUAGCCCUCAGAAGCCCAGAUUAUGUGGGGAUAUCUUGCAGACAGUAGUUACUCCCACCCAAGGUAAACACGAUUCUGACUUACAUAACUAUAGUUUUACCUGGUUUUGAACUCAUGUGUAAAUGGAAUAAUGCCCUCUGGACUUUUUUUUUUUUUUUUUGCUUGACUUCUUUUACUCGAUGUUGUGUCUGAGAUUCAUUCAUGUUGUUGCAUGUAGUUUGUUAUUUUUAAAAAUAGCUCUGUAGUUGUGGUUAUCUAUCCCUGCAUAACACACUAGUUUUGAUUAUUGGUUAUUGCGUAACACACCACUCCAAACUUACUAGUGUAAAAUAACAACCAUUUUAUUAUGCUCAUGGAUUCUGUGGAUUGGGAAUUUGGUGGUUAUGGCUUAUCACUGCCCUACAAUGCUUGGGGUCUAGAAUCAUUUAGAGGCUUCUCCACUUUCCUGUAUGGUACCUUGACUAGAACGUCUAGAAGACUGGGAUCAUCUGAUACUGUUGACCAAACCUACAUGUGGGGUCAGGAGGUUUUGGCUUUUCACAGCAUGUUGGCUGAGUACCUUGACUAGAACGUCUAGAAGACUGGGAUCAUCUGAUACUAUUGACCAAACCUACAUGUGGGGUCAGGAGGUUUUGGCUUUUCACAGCAUGUUGGCUGAGUGUCCAGAGGAAGCUUCCUGAGAGUGGCUUAUCUUCAGAAGUCAUAUAAUCUCACCUCCACCAUACUCUAUUGGUUGACAAAGACACAGCCUGCCUGGAUUGAAGGGGAGGGGACAUAGACCUCAUGUCUUUAUGAGAGGUGUGUCAAAGAAUUUGUGGUCAUUUUUAAAAACUACCACAAAUUACAUAGCAAAAUUCAUUUAUUCAUUCCAUUUUAGGUAUUUGAAUAGUUUCUAUUUUGAGGCAAUUAUGAACAAUGUUGCUAUAAUCAUAUACUUAUGUAUAUGUAUGUAUCUUUUGGCAUACUUUUAUAUUCAUUUUGGUUGGGUAUAUAUGUAGGAGUAGAAUUCCUGGUCAAAAUGUAUAUGCAUCUAGCUUGCUUGCUUGCUUGCUUUCUUUUUUUUUUUUUUUUUUCUGAAACGAAGUCUCCCUUUGUCACCCAGGCUGGAGUGCAGUGGUAUGAUCUUGGCUUACUGCAACCUCUGCCUCCCAGGUUCAAGUGAUUCUCCUGCCUCAGUCUCACAAAUAGCUGGGAUUAUAGGCGCCUGCCACCACGCCUGGCUCAUUUUUGUAUUUUUAGUAGAGACAGGGUUUCUCCAUGUUGGCCAGACUGGACUCCAACUCCUGACCUCAAGUGAUCUGCCUGCUUCGGCCUCCCUAAGCGCUGGGGUUACAGGUGUAAGCCACUGUACCUGGCCAUGUGUCUAGUUUUAAUAGACACUGCCAAAUUGUUUUUCAUCCUUGUUGUACCUAUUUAUACUUUUACCAACAUAUGAAAGUUCCGGUUACUCUGCAGCUUUGCUUCCCUUGAUAUUGUCAGUUAAAUAUUACAAAAAAUUAAUCACUAGUGGCUGUAUAGAAGAUCUUAGUGUGGUUUUCGUGGGCAUUUCUCUAAUCACUGAUAAUUUGAGCACUUCUUCAUAUGCUUGUUGGCCAUUUGGAUACCCUCUGUUAUAAAGUUCCUGUUCAAGUCUUUUGUCCAUUUUCAACAGAUUGGAUUGUCUUUUUUCUUAUUGAAAUGUGGAGUUUAUAAGGUAUCUGGAUAUGAAUCCUUUGUCGAAUAUGUGAAUUAUAAAAAUCUUCCUGUCUUACAGCUUGUCAUUUCACUCUCAUAAAGUUUUUGAUGAACUGAAAUUCUGAAUUUUAAUCAAUUCCAAUGUAUCCAUCUUUUCCUUUACGGGUAGUGUUUUUUUGUGUUUAAGAAGUUUUUGCUACUCUAGGGCGAUGAAGCUAUUUUCUUAUGUUAUCUUCUAGAAGCUUUAGUAUUUUGCCUUUCAGAUUUAGGUCAAAGUCCCCAGGAAUUUGUUUGUGUGUUAUGAGGUAGGGAUCAAGCCUUCUUUUACUUUUUUCAUAUGGUUAUCUAUACAAGUAGUAACAGGUGGCAUUGGGUCUGUUGGACACAAGCCUGGGAGUUAGGAUUCCAGUAUUCUCCACCUUAGAUUACCUUUAAUGAGCCUUCUGCACUUGGGCAUAUUCUUAAAUCCGUCUUGACUCAGCUUCAUUUGUGAAAUGAAGGAUUUGAAUGGAAUGUUUUCUGAUUUUCAUUCUGACUGUGGUUUGUUAGAUCUCUACCUACUUUUGUAGUUGUAUUGAGGCUUGUUAGAAUCUUCUUAUAUCUGGAUUGUGUUAUCUAAAAUAUUCAUAACAUCUCCCAGCUUUAUGUUGUUCCCAGUUCGAAUGUGCUAUCUAGAACUUAGCUGCUGAUGAAAGAUAGUUUUAUUGAUCACGUUGGCAAGUCCAAGAUCACCUGUUCUUCUGAUUUUUUUUUUUAAUUUUUUUUUGAGAUGGAGUGUCACUCUGUUGAUAGUGCAGUGGCGCUAUCUCGGCUCACUGCAACCUCCGCCUCCUGGGUUCAAGCGGUUCUCCCACCUCAGCCUCCCAAGUAGCUGGGAUUACAGGUGCACGCCACCACGCCCAGCUAAUUUUUUGAAUUUUUAGUGGAGAUGGGAUCUCACCAUGUUGGCCAGGCUGGUCUUGAACUCCUGACCUCAAGUGAUCCACCCACCUUGGCCUCCCAAAGUGCAGGGAUUACAGGUGUGAGCCACCGCGCCCAGCCUCUGAUCUUACUAAUAUACUGUGUCCCUUGCCAGGAGCUCAUCAUGCUUUGUUUAGUAAGUCAUGGUAGAAGACACCAAUUCCAUUAACAAAAAAAUUAGCUAUCUCCUGCAGAAGGGAGCAAAUUCCAUUUUUGAAAGUCAUCUGCACAUACUAUUCAUCUUACUUGUCCCUACCUUCAGUUUCGUACUUGAACUUUUAAGAAUCACAUACACAGCAUAGAGUUUCAUGAAUCAGCAGAAGUCAUUCAAGAUCAGUGAGUUGUAGUCUUGGCAAAUUCUCUCUUCCAUCUUGGAAAGUGGCAUACGUUCCAAAUUACUGUAUAAUAUGUUUGUGUCUCUAAGAAGAGUGAGUCAGGAACUACCCUGGAUGACAGAACAGAAAAUCUACCAUUUGCUGGUUUCUUUGUGUUCUUAGUGGCCUGCUUUGAGGUGCUUUUAACCCUUCUUUGAAAAUAUUUAGUUUAGUUUCCACAGAACGCUAUAAUCCAGUGUAGCUAUUUUUCUUUGUUAUCCUUGCUAUCACAUUUUCCCUCUCAUUAACCUUUUUUUUUUUAAAGCAAACAGCUUUAGUGAGAUAUAACUUACAUACCAUACAAUUCAUUCAUUAAAAGGUAUAAUUCAGUAGCUUUUAGUGUAUGCACAGGACUGUAACCAUCACCAUAAUCUAAUUUUAGAAUGCUUUCAUCAGUACUAAAACCCCCUACUCAUUAACAGUCAUUCUCCAUUCCCUACUUGAUCCCUAAGAAACCACGAAUAGUUUUGUCUAUAAAUUUAUCAAUUCUGGAAAUUUUACGUAAUUGGAAUCAUAUAAUAUGUAGUGUUUUGUGACCAGUUUCUUAACGUGUGUUCAGGGUUCAUCCCUGUUGUACAUGUGUUAAUACUUUAUUUCUUUUUAUUGCUGAAUAAUAUUCCAUUGUAUAGGUGUACCAAAUUUGAUUUAUCCAUUCAUCAGUUGAAGGACUUUGGGGUUGCUUUUGCUUUUUGACUAUUAUGAUUAGUGCUGCUAUGGACAUUUAUGUACAAGUUGUUGUGUGGGUAUGUGUUUUCAUUUCUCUUGAGUAUACCUAGGUAAUUCUUUAAGUUCUUUAGGGACUACCAAACUUUCCCAAAGUGGCUGUAUUGUUUUAUAUUCUUACUAACAAUCUGUAAGGAUUCAGAUCUCUCUAGAUCCUACCAAAACUUGUUACUGUCUUUUUGUUUAUAUAUGUCCUAGUGGGUAGGAAGUGGCAUCUCGUUGUGGUCUUGACUUUCAUUUCCCUAACAACUAAUGAUACUGAGCAUCUUUUUGUUUGCUUGUUGGCCAUUUGUUUAUCUGUUUUGGAGAAAUGUCUGUCCAAAUCCUUUACCCAUUUUUAAACUGGCUUAGUUGUCUUUUUGAGUUCAUUAACCUUUUAAUGUUCACUCUGAUUUACUUUUAACUCAAAAUGUUUUUUCUUUUUCUUCCAUUUUGUUCAGAGACUGUUCGUUCUGUAUUAAGCAGGAUGGUUAAGAGGGUUUUCAAGCCCUUUUAUGUUUUCUUGGCAACAGGUUCCAUUAGCAACAUACAUACAUGUGGAUUACUUUAGAUUGGAAAAUGUACAUCUACUGGUUAUUGGAAUAGAUCAUUUGUGGUUCAUACUGGUUAUAUUAAUAAAAUGAACUCUGCUCCUUUUCCUACAAACCAGUAGGUAAAAUGCUUGGCUUUGACUUUAAUCCUAGCCUUUCAUUUUACAGGUAAGGAAAAAAGACCUGGAGAAGUUGGGUCUUGUCUUAAGUUCACAACAGGUAGACCUGGACCAUGACUUUAAUUCAGCCCAUUCUUAAGAACUAUCAGUUGGUUUCACAUCAUGUGGCAGAUAUGUUAGAUUGAAGGGAUACCAAGGUAAGACAGGGUCCCUGAUUUGGCGAUCCUCACAAACUGUGUCACAAGAGAUUGACAUAUACAUAACUAAUGGUAAUACAGUAUCACAAUUGCUGUGAAUUGUGAACAAGGGUGUGUAGUCAGUCCAGUGCUCUUAACACUGCUCGGUGCUGACUGGGAUUUUCACCUUACUUUCUUUUGCAUAUAGGCAGAAUUAGAUUCUUGAGUAGUUGAUUUUGUUUGGGUCAUUUAGUAAGAAAUGAUAACACAAAUGCCAUCAUUCAAACCCUGAGAUUACAGAAGAAACAGACUUUAGAAUCUUCAGGGUUUUGGACUAGAAUCUAGAAGAUAGUCUCAUUAAGUGCAUAUUUUAUAUGUAUUAUUUUCUUAGCUUUUUUCAUAUAUUCUUCAGUGGCGUAUACAUCAAGUUUUUUUCAGCUGAAUUUGUGUUAGUAUAUUAAAAAAACAAAACUUUUCGGAAGACGUUUUAUUUACAUCAGUGAUUUAUUUCAUUACUACGUUUGUCCUUUGGAUUUUUGGAAGUCAUAUUUCUUUUCACUUGACAGAGUUAGGCCAUGGGAUAUGUAUUUAUAGUAAUGUGUGAGUAUGUUUAGGUUUGAUCUUUUAUACUAUUUUUAUGGCAUUUAUAUUUAUGGCUGUGUUAUUAGUCAUUAAAGCAAAUAUUUUUCCACCUUAAGACUUCUUGUUUUGCACAUGAUUUAUUCUGCAGUAUGUGCUCUCUUUUAAUUAGCAAAAAGGCAUUUUUACAAAAAUUACACUUUCCUUGCAACUUACUGGUUGUAAGGCCGUGGACAAAUUAUUUAAUUUCACUUAUCCUUGGUUUCCUUAUAUAAUGAUACAGUCAGUAUCAUUAUACCUUUGUUUUAUGGUUAUCCUAAGAAUUAGAGAUAAUGUGUUUAAGUUACCCAGCAUAUAGCUUGCCAUAUAGAUGCUUGAAUAUUGAUGGUAUUAAUUGUAAUAUAUUAGUUCAUUUAUACAUAAGAGCUAUAAAUUCUAGUUAAUGGUUAAUCGAUUCUUUGUGAUAUAGAUUACUCAUUUAGGAUUAAUUGAGCAAAAAUAAGUGAUCAUAUUAAUGUAAGAACUUGAUAUCAGUAUUCAUUUUCAGUUACUUGUCUUUUAGAGACUGUAGUACUUUAAAGACUAGAGACUAUUGCUCUUUAAAGACUGACCUCAUCUUUAUCUUCAAAACAUGAAGGUAUGAUCCUGUCUGCAGAUUAAGGUAUUGAGAGUUAUUUUUCUAUGUUGUCAAUUGCAGUGUUUUAACUUGUGGCAGUUGACAGGGCUGACUGUGUUGAUCCUGAUGCUUUAGAAGCACUGGUAAAUUCUAGACUAAUAUUGGAAAGAAUUACUUGACAUUUUAUUUACUAAAGUUCUUUUUGUUAUUCAUGAAGAAUUCUUAAAAAAUACCUCAAUUGAAAAAUUAAUACAUGCACACAAUAAUAAAUUUAGACAAUAUAAAAGAGCAAAGAAUGAAAAUUAAGCUUCCCACCCUUAAGGCAUUCUCUGCUACUAAUUGAUUAUAUAGCCUCCUAGUAAUGUGCUAUAUGUACACGCGUGGGGAUACAUUGUUGCACAGCUCCCAGGGGUGCAGUCAUACAUAUUCAAGCAUAUGCAGCAUAUGUAUAAUGGUCCUUUUAUAUGAAUAGGAAUGUUCUCAUACAAGGUUCUUUCCUUGUAUUUUUCACUUAAUGAUAUAUCUUGGCGAAUAUUCCAUGCCAAUGUAUGUAGAGCUACCUUAUUUUUAAAACUGCCUAAUAUUCCAUUCUGUGGAUAUGCCAUGCUUCAUUUAAUAUUAUGUUGGUGCAAAAGUAAUUGCGGUCCAACCUAAAAGUCCCCUCUUGAUGGUAAUUAAGGAUCUUUCUAGUCUUUUAUUGUAUAUAAUGCUGCAGUAACUAUCCAUGUAUAUUUGACAGUACGUGAGUAUCCCUGCAUGAUAAAUUACUGGAAGUACACUUUGUGAGCAAAAGGGAGUAUGCAUUUAAAAUUUUGAUAAUGCCAAAUUGUUAUGCCUUUUUCCUCAUACUCUUACCAACCCAGUGCAUUUUCUUAUUUUUUGAAUAUGACUAAUGUGAUAACUAAAAAAUGUCAUUUUAAUUGUAAAUUAAGUCUCAUUGUAAUUUUAAUUUGCAUUUUAUUAAUGAAGCUGAGUCUAUUUGUUAUUGAUUUCCAGGAUAUAUUGUUAGUGAAAGAAAUCAUGGUGAAGAACAAGGUGUAUAAUAUUCUAUCUCUCAUCUAGGAAAUGAGGGAUGCAGAUAAAUGUAUUUUAUUUGUUAUUUAAAAAGAGAAAACAGGAAGGAUAACCCCAAAACUAGUGAAAGCCAUUAUUUGAGGGGAAAAAUAAUAAAGACGGAGGGGUAGAAUCUAGGAUUCUCUGAAGAUACCUUAUAUUGUUUGGGCUUUGGAAAUGUAAAUGUUUUAUACAUUUUUAAAACUUAAAGAGGAAAAUAUAUCAGUUAAAUAUUUAGGUUGACAUUGUUAGGAACCAAGGUUUUUAACAAAUGAGAAAAAAAGCCGGGUGCGGUGGUUCGUGCCUGUAAUCCCAACACUUUGGAAGGCUGAGGUGGGAGGAUCACUUGAGCUCAGGAGUUUGAGACCAACCUGGGCAACAUAGCCAGACCUCACUCUACUAAAAAAAAAAAGAAACAGAACAAAACAAAUUCGUGGGCAUGGUGGCACUGGUCUGUAGUCCCAGCUGCUUGGAAGGUUGAGGUGGGAGGAUUGCUUAGGGCCGAGGCUGCAGUGAGCCAUGAUUCUGCUAUUGCACUCAGCCUGGGUGACAGGGAGACCCUGUCUGGAAAAAAAAAAAAAUCUUCUUGCUCUGUCCACUCAAAAAACCUAGAAAUAAUAUUUUAGUGCCCAGAUUUUGGUCUCCGAGUACCACUUUCAACUAAAAGGAAAUAGGGCCCCUUGUAGAAGUGGCUGAUUGUAGGCUUGAGACAGGAAAAUGUACAGAAGGAACCUGGAACAUUUUGUACUAGGAAAGCAAGGAAAAGCUCCAAGACUAGUAGGGUUGUAUCAGGAAACAGUGGCCACAUUGAAGGGGCCCCCGUUGUCCAGUGGGAAAGAAAAAAGAAAUGAGCAGCCCCUGAUGUUCAGAAGCCUCACCGGUAGGCCAUGUUCUCCUACUAAACAUAAGCGGUCUCACAGAAUACCUUCAACAAAGUUUCUCAGAGAUCAUAAUAAAAUGAGGCAAAGCAUAGACAAAAACCAAGACCACUGUGCCACCUACAAAAUACUUAGCCAAAAUGAAUGACUACCGCUGCUUUACCCAUUACAGUUUUAUCUUCAUUCUCAUCUCCCCUCCCUUAGGUAAGAUUUAUUGAGAUACGUAACCACAGAAUUACCCUACUUCCUGACAGCAUCCAAUGUAGAGAAACUCCUCCUUCUUUAGACCCUCCCCCAAAUUACUAAACUGAGGCCCAAAUUGUGUAAUUGAUUUUAACAUCCUCUUACUGAGAUGCCCCAUGGUGCCCUGUGGUGUGUGUUCUCCCUCACUGCAAUGAGUAAUAAGCCUGUCUCGUUUAAUUAUUGGUGGUCUUGGCUGAAGGGCAUUGAUAACAGGUAGAGUAAUUUGAGCAACAAUAUCAGUAACAAAAAAUACAAGGAACAGAUUAAGUGACAGUAUAGGGUCACAAUCAGCAAAAUUCAAAAUGGGAAAUUUUACAGGACAAAUGACAAGAAGAAGGACAAAAAAGAGAACAGUGGCACUCAAAGAGACUCAAAGACACAUCAGCCACGUGCAUUGACUAGUAUUUGGGUCCUGAGUCAAAGUCAACUGUGAGAAGACAUUCUUUGAGAAAACUGGAUAAAUUUGAACCCUUCUUAUUAGAUGACAUUAAGGAAUUACUGUUAAUUUUGUUAGGUGUGGCAAUAAUAUAUGGUGGAUUUAUUUUUAAAAAGUACCUGUUAAAAGUAUUUACAUAUGAAAUGAUGUGUUGUCUGAGGUUUGCUUUAAAAUAAUCUUGGAAGGGGUUAGUAGAAACAAACAAAUUGGCCAUGUGUUGUUGAUAGUUGUUGAAAUUAGCUGAUGUUUAGGUGGACACUCAUUAUAUCACUUCUCUACUUCAUAUGUAUUUGAAAAUUCUUCUAAGGAGAAGUUUUUUUCUUUAAAGCCAUAUUUAUUUCUUUUUCUGUGAGUGUGCCUCUUCAUAUUCUUCCAUUUUUCUGUUGGGCUUUAGUCUUAUAAUUUAAAGGGUUCUUUAAAUACUAAGAAAAUUUGCCUUUAGUCAUAUGUUUUGCAGGUAUUUUUAAUUUGUUUUUUGAAUUUGUUUAUGGCUUUUUUUUAAUCUGUGGAGAAUUUCUAUUUUUAUUUUGUUAAAUUUAUCAGUUUUCUUUAUGGCUUGCGUGUUUUGUGUGUUUAGAAAAAUCUUCUUGUCUCUGAGAUUCUGAAAAGUUCUUUCAUGUUUUCAUGAAUUUUUUUAAUGACCACAGUACACUUCUGUUAUACUUUAUUUAGUCACCUUAAUUUCCUCUUAGAGUAUUUGGAAAUAUUCUCCCAUAGAGCCCUGCCCCAAGACUAUAUAGGGAAAAAUGUUGUUCAGUAGCUGUUCUAUCAGAUCUAUUGAUAGAUUAUUAUAUAGUGAACAUCCAGAGAAUUAAUUGUAAAAGUUUGCUCACUAAUUUUGCUCCCUAAAUAGAAUGAAUGAGAAAUCUAUUUACCAGAUUUUGAAAAUAUGCUAAGUGUUAUGUAAAAGUAUUAGCUAUAUAGUUCACAGUUUCUAAUUUUAGAAAAGUUUCAGUGUUUGCUUUAUAUAAAGAAGCAUUCCUUUGAGCUCUUCUCAUGGGCCAUAAGGUCAAGGAGCCAGGUGUCACCGCUUUUUGAAGUUGACAUCUUUUGGCUUGCUCCUUUCCUAGGUCUGACUCUCUUGGAUAGGCACAACAGUGAUUCUGUUUUCUGGUCUCUGUAGGAAUGGAUGUUACUGUAGUGUCUUCAUCACUUUCGUUUCUGGGAGACCUGUUGAGACCCAGGAAUGGAUCCUUCUACCUACUAUCUCAAAAGUCAGAAACGGAAAUACAGUUAAGGCUUCAGGGAAUGCUUCCCUUGUAGGGGAAAGUGAUAGCAGUGAGGUGUCUUGGGCUUGUGUUUGCAAAUGUACCACACUGUGCAUUCUCAGUUGAAAACUAACUCUGCAGUUAGUGUUUCUCUUUUAGAACUUUUAGAAGUUUUUUAAGGAAUAAAAGUUGAGAAAGUACAUUUGAUACUAUAUUUUAAGCAUUUUACUCACUAUACCAAAACAUUUUAUAACCUAACGUUGAUCACUUUUCUAAUACAAGUAAAAAAAUUUCUGACUAGGAAGAAAUUUUUUCUUUUCUGAAGAUAGCCACUUUCUUUUUCAGAGUUAGAAACGUGAGUCUUCACCUAGUUCUUUCCAGCUUAGGUGUGAAAACAUGACUAGUGUGACAAUUGCUGCUAAAGAUUGUAUCACAGUUUGAGUUUAGCUUAAUGUUUUUCAGGGAUAAAUCUAUGAAUUUAUGGGAUCAUUAUCUCUGGAGGUUCACUUCUAUAUCUCAUGGUUUGUUGUGUUAUAUUUUGAUACUUAUUUUUUUAAUGUUAUAAAGGUACCAUAUAGCCAUGAAUUUUUUUAUACUUUCAUUGAUAUGCAUAAUUCUCCUCUGAGUGAAACCUGGGGACAGAUUGGGUGUUCCUAACAGGAACCUGGGGGCAGUUUCCUUAGGUUUUUUAUGUUUAGUGAUUUUGGUCAUAAGUGAAUUUUAAUAUCUAAUGAAUAUCCUUACAGUUCUGUCUCAAUCAUAGGAUUUUUGGGAUCAAAAUGAAGAAAAUAUAUGAGGACCCUCUGUGUCACUGGGAAGUGGCUUUAUAAACUCAAGAUUCUGUAUUUUAUUUUUCAAAUGAUUUCUUAGCACUAAUCAAAUGCAUUAAUCAACUUCUGAUUAGCUGGCACAUUUAUAAGAGGAUUGUCUUUAGAUGUAUUGCUUUCAAAUUGUUCCUGAUGUAAUUUAGCAAAGGAGGUGAUGGAGUUCUUUGUUGACUGACUAUCUUUCGUUUGAUUUUAUUCUGACUUACUGUAGUUUGGCAGGAGGCCAGUUAUACCAAAAUAUGUAAUUACUUCUUAAUCCCAAAUAAGUUUGAAAUAUAAAUGAGUCAUUUUGUCUUAGGGAUAUGAUGGGUUGGGAAAAAAGUGGUGUUUUUGGCUCCUCCUAAAUCACUCAUGAAUUUAUUUUUUACCCAACUUCUAAAAUGAACUGGAAAGGUCUUUUAUUAAAAUCCUCAGAUACGGUAGACUUGUAUGUAAUAGAGCAAUUAAAGUGAAAAUGAAUGACUUAAUGAAGAAAGUAAGAUGUACCAGAAUAUCUAGGUCAGUGGGUCAGUCUGUGCAUCACAGUACCCUGUGUAGCAUGAAAAUAUAAAGAUGCUGGGGCUGUUGUGGAGUAAGGCCUUUACUGUUCCAAAGUUCCACUGAUAAUUAGGUUGGUGCACAAAUAAUUGCGGUUUUGGACUGUGAAUUUUAAAUCAUUAUAACUAGGCUCAAACACAUCUUUAUCAAAAUAGGAGCCAUUGCAGUCAACACAUUUUUGCCAAUGAGAAGUAAGUUAGUUUAUUCCUGUAGUGUAAAAAUCCGUGUUUUGGGAUUCGAUGAACUCUUGGAAAGCAUUUUCUGCAUCCUGCUGGUUGUGCAAGCGUUUUCCCUGCAAAAAUUUGUUGAUAUGCUUGAAAAAGUGGUAGUCGGCUGGUGAGAGGUCAGGUGAAUAUGGCGGAUGAGACAAAACUUUGUAGCCCAAUUCAUUCAACUUUUGGAGUGUUUGUUGUGCGACGUGCAGUCGGGCGUUACCCUGGAGAAGAAUUGGGCCCUUUCUGUUGACGAAUGCUGGCUCCAGGUGUUGCAGUUUUUGGUGCAUCUCAUCGAUUUGCUGAGUGUACUUCUCAGAUGUAAUGGUUUCGCCAGGAUUCACAAAGCUGUACUAGGUUAGACUGGCAGCAGACCAUCAAACAGUGACCAUGACCUUUUUUUGGUGCAAGUUUGGCUUUGGAAAGUGCUUUGGAGCUUCUUCUCAGUCCAACCACUAAGCUUGUUGUUGCCGAUUGUUGUAUAAAAUUCACUUUCAUCACUAUCCGAUCGAGAAAUGGUUCAUUGUUGUAGUGUAGAAUAAGACAAGAUGACACUUGAAAAUGAUGAUUUUUUUUUUUUAAUUUUUGCUCAGCUUAUGAGGCAUCCACUUAUAGAGCUUUUUCACCUUCCCAAUUUGCUUCAAAUGCUGAAUGACUGUAGAAUGGUCAACGUUGAGUUCUUCGGCAACUUCUCUGUAGUUGUAAGAGGAUCAGCAUCGAUGAUUGCUCUCAAUUGAUCGUUGUCAACUUCCAAUGGCCAGCCUCUACCCUCCUCAUCUUCACGCCUCUCAUUUCCUUUGAAAAACUUCUUGAACCACACCACACUGUAUGUUCGUUAGCAGUUCCUGGGCCAAAUGCGUUGUUGAUGUUGUGAGUUGUCUCUGCUGCUUUACAACCCAUUUUGAACUCGAAUAAGAAAAUUGCUCAAAUUUGCUUUUUGUCUAACAUCAUUUCCAUAGUCUAAAAUAAACAAAAUAAACAGCAAACAAUAAGUCAUUAGCCAAAAAACAUAAAGUGAGAAAUGUCCAUUAAAAUGAUGUAUAACAUAACCACAUUUAUUUAAGAAUGUAUUAUAAUAUCAAACAGCAAAUUCCAACAAUGCAAAAACCACAAUUAUUUUUGCACUAACCUAAUAAUUUUAAUGUAUAGUUAAGAUAGAUGUUACUGCCUUAGAUGAUGGAUCGUUAGGCAUUUGGCUUUAUAAUUUUGUUCUGAAUUUCCUAGCAUUCACUGCAAAAGAGGUAACAGGAGUUUCAUAGCUCUUGAUAUCUUAAACACUUGCAUCAUUGGAAGAGACACUUUUUUCCCUACCAUGAACCCUAGAGAGUUUGAUUUUGUAGAUGUCCACAACUGUUCACUAUCUUUAAUAAAUACUUUUAUUAAAGGCUUCAGAAACAUUCUUUCCCUGGGAAGUUUUUUAUUGAUCCUUGUUUGAAGUUGAUACAUAAUAUUAUAUCAUAACUGUGUGAUGCUGUUUCUGCAUAUAGCUGAAUGCAGCUUUUUGAGACUAAAGGUUGCAUUUCCUUCAUCUUUGAAUUUCCAGCCCCUAGCACAGUUCCUGGCACAUAUUUUGGAGGUAUUUUAUAAAUGCCUUUGGAAAAAAGGAGUUCAAGUGUUUAAUUUCCUGGCAAACUAAAUAGCUAUAAAGAGAGAGCUUAGAAAGUCUAGAGUAAGAGAUGAUUAGCAUGCUUCCUAGACCAUCUGUCACUAAUACCAAUUGUUUCUACUUGGCACUGCAGACUUGUUUUUUGAGGGGGAGGGCAGCUUGUGUAAAGUUAAAAAAAACAAAACAAAACAAAAUACCAGAACUCUUAGGUUAUUCUAUACCCCUCUGUUUAGUGGCUAAAAAGUCAUUGCUGUUUUCUAAAAAACAUUGACAUUCUUAUUCAGUAAAGAUAAAUGCAAUUAUUGCUUUUUCCAAUAGCAAUACAGUUGUAAUAACUGGUAGCUGUUUCUGCCUUGCCCCCUUACAGUCUAUUCUUGAUGCGUCAACCAGAGUGAUCCAUUCAAAGUGCAAGUCAGAACAUGUACACUCCUCUGCUCAAGACCUUCCAAGAUUUCCCCAUUCAGAGUUAACGUUGAAGUCCUUACAAUAGCCUGAGUGUUGGGCAUGUUCUCCACCUCUGUGCUUCUUUACAUCUGACCCCAGCCAUUGCUCUCCCCUGGCUAAUUCUUCCUCAGCUGCACCAGUCCCCUUGCUGUUUCUAGAACAAGCUGGACAUGUUCUUGCCUUAACGCCUUUGUAGUCGCUCCUCCCUCAAUGUGGGAUGCUAUUCCUCUAGAGCAUCUGUGUGGCUAGAUUCUCUCACUUUUUUUUUUUUUUUAACAAGUUUUUGCUUAAAUGUCACUUUCUUGUGAGGCUUUACCAGACCAUCUUUUUAAAUUUCAUUCCCUCCCGCCCCCAACUCCCUGUCCCUGCCUUUUUUUUUUUUUCCUUAGCCCUUAUACCAUUGGACAUAUGACAUGUUUUAAUUUUUAGAAAAUUAUUUUUCUCUACUGAAUAAAAUAUAAGCUCCAUGAAGGCAGGAGUUUUUGUCUGCUUUGUUCACUUUUUAUUCUUGUCUUGUAGAACAGUUCCUGCACAGAGUGUGCUGUCAAUAAAUACUUGUUGAGUAAACAAAUUAAUUAAGCAGGCAGUAUGUAUUGUAAUAAUGUAGAAUUCCAAUGGGACUCAGUAUUGUUUUUAUUUUAAAUUUUAAGAGGGGUGUAGCAUGGUAAAGUUUUUGUAUUUCUUGUCAAAAAGUUGCAGACCAUUCACUCUAAUAGCACUACUAAAUUACUGAUAUUUACAUUAAAGGGAAAAUAGGGUCUAGUCCUAUUCUCUACUUUUUAGGCACAGAAUUUGAUUCAUUGCAAAACCAUUCCUAUCGUGAGGUGACUUGUGACAGAGGCACUACAGAAGCACUUAACAUUUUGGAUUUGUAUCAAGCUUAUAUAGUUUAUAGAUGGAAUGUAUUUUUAGAAUGGACUAACACAUUAGCAAAAAAUAUAACAAAUGUAAAAUCUUUGGUGAGAAUUAAGUCAGCAGGAGAAUUUUUCUUGACUUAGGUGUUCAGUGCAUGAUUUUCAAUUUGAUUGAAGUGUUGUGAACUACAAUGCAAGUAUACAGCAAGUUCCAAACCUUGUAGAAAUCCAUUUACCCUGUGGUGAAAUUCAGAGUCCUGACAGUAGCCUUCAAGGCCCUACUUGAUCUCUUGCUCCUGUGCUAACCUUUGGGACUUGAUCUCCUGCUUCCCCCUUGCUCACGCCACACCAGCCACACUGGCAUUCUUACUCUUUGGUUGCCAGGUGUGCUCCCACCUUAGGGUCUUUGCACAACUCGUCCCUCUGCCUAUACUCUCUGCCCAGAUACUCACAUGGUCCUCUUCCUCAACUCCUUCAAGUCCUUGUUCCAAUGAGCAAAGUCCUUUCAGAGGAGGCUGACCAUGACCACUCUGUUUCACUGCAAGCUUUCCCCUUCUACCUUCUACUCCCUAUCCUCUAUCUCCCUUUACCUGCUUUAUGUUUUUAAAACAUGACUGGAUUUUCUGAAAUAUUAGGUAACAUAUGCAUUAUUUGUUCUUUUUAUCUGUCUCUUCCUGCCAGAAUGUGUCAAAAGAGAAGGACCUUUGUUUUGUUCCUUGAGGUAUAGCAAGUGCCUAGAACAGUGCUUGGCACAUUGUAGAUUAUCAGUGACUAUUUGUAGAGUGAGUGAAUGAACAGACUAUGUCAUUACCCUUCAUGAAUUUACAUAAUCCACAGUUAACAUUUAUUUAUUGCUGUGAUAACUAGUAGAUUUAUGUAAUUAGCAUCUAUAAGAAUAACCUCUGAAAAAAAUACCAAUUGUAAUGCUUUUCCAGUUGUGUGUGUAUGGGGGCAGGAAUGAUUCUGUAGUCAUCAGGAACACGUUGGUAUUAUCUUGAUUCAACUUAAUUUCUGCCUUUUUUAUCUGCUGCAUCUAGAAACUGUUUUCUUUUUUAAAAAAUUGUGAUAAGAAACAUAGAAGAUUUCCCAUCUUAACCAUUUUUAAGUGUACACAGUAGCGUUAAGUGUAUUCAUAUUGUUGUGAAGCAGAUCUCUAGAACUUAAUUUGCAAAUUCGAAACUCUAUAUACCACUAAACAACAACUCUCUUUUCUCCCUCCCUCCAGCCUCUGGCUUAUUUCACUUAGCAUAACUGUCCUCAAGAUUCAUCUGUGGUGUAGUGUGUGUCAGAAUUUACUUCUAUUUUUCAAGGCUGAAUAAUAUUCCAUUGUAUAUACAUGCCACAUUUAUUCAUUCAUCUGUUAAUGGACACUCAGGUUGCUUCCACCUUUUACUAUUAUUGUGGAUAGUGCUGCUGUGCACAUGGGUGUACAGAUACCUCUUUGAGACUACAAACUUUUUCCUAGAGAUCUGUUAACUUAAAGGAAUAAACAUCAAUUAUUUUUUCAAAUAAAUGUCCUGAAUUUCCAAAGAUCUUAAUUUUAUUGAGUAGCACAUUUUUAAAUAUAUAAUUUAUUUUCACAUAAUAAAAUUUGUAUUUUGGUGUAAGCUGUGGAAAUGUAGGUGGUCUGCUUUUUUAACAUGAUAAAACCCUGGAAAACUGUAUAUGAUAAAGUGGAACAAGCUCCCUGAAUGAAAGCUCAUUUCAUCUUGAAAAAAGAAUUUACUGUAUUCCUCAAAUUGCCUAGGACUGUGAGUAGCCUAAAUGGUAGACUGGAAUCCAGGAUACUACUGUAUUUUGAAAGCAAAAGGAAGAGAAUGUUUCAAGAAAGAAAGAAUGAGCAGUGUUGAGUGCUUCUGGGCAGGCAAAUGAGAUGAUUCAGUGUCAGCUAGAUUUCAUAGCAUGGAAGUCACUGGUGACCUCAGCAAGGGUUAUUAGAGAGGAAUCAUGAAGGCGGAUCUCGGAGUGAGUUGGAUAAGUAGGUGAAAGGAAAUAUUGGCAAGUACAGACGAUUAUUGAAAUGGCAAGUACAGACAUUUGGCAUUGAAAGGGAAAAGAAAGGAUGAUAGCAGAGAUAGCAGAGGGGGAUUAAAAACAUUAAUUUUUUUUUUUUUUUUUUCCCUCUGUCGCCCAGCCUGGAGUGCAGUGGCGCCGUCUCGGCUCACUGCAAGCUCUGCCUCCUGGGUUCACACCAUUCUCCUGCCUCAGUCUCCCGAGUAGCUGGGACUACAGGCAUCCACCACCACGCCUGGCUUAUUUUUUGUAUUUUUAGUAGAGACGGGAUUUCACCAUGUUAGCCAGGAUGGUCUCGAUCUCCUGACCUCGUGAUCCACCCGCCUCGGCCUCCCAAAGUGCUGAGAUUACAGGUGUGAGCCACCGCACCCGGCCAAAAACAUUAAUUUUUUAAAAUGGCAGAGCCAUAAGCAUUUUUAAUAGCUGAUGGGAAGGAUCUAGUUGAGGGAGACAUUGAAUAUAUUAGAGAAGGAUUAAUUAAUAGUGUAAGUCUUGAGAAGGUUGGAGGGGAUGGGAUCCAAAGCAAAGGUGAAGGACUUGAUGUUUGAUAGGAGGAGGAUAGUUUCUUUCAAUGUGAUAGGAGAGAAGGAAGCUAGGAUUGGCUUGAAGUGGGUGCAGGUGGUUUGUAGGUGUGGCUCUUAGAAAGAUAGGGAAUUCCCAUCUGAAGUUUCUGUUUUCUCUCUAAACUAGAGUAGGUCAUCUGUUGAUAAUUAUGGCUUAGGAAGGGGAAUUAGAGUUUUGAGGAAGAAUAAAUAGAGUUUGACAUAGUCAUUGUAGAGGGUGGUUGCUGGACUUUUGAGGAAUGACAUUGUCCUUUGCAGUUGGGUGAUGUAUAUUAAACAUAAAGUUAGAUAUCUGGUAGUUGGGGAAAAAUACUAAACUUUUUUGCUGUUUAAUUUUAUGGAUUUAGUGAAUUCCUGCUAACUACAAUGUAUUGUGACUAAGACAUUUCUCAUAUACGAGGAGCUUAUAAGCUUAUAGGGAAAGUUAUUUGUCACAUGCAAUAAGAGGUACAAACAGUACUGAAACUUCAGGUCAUAUCUGACUUCAGAAGAGAUAGGUCUUUAGGUAUGGGGAAAAUGUCAAUCAAUGUAUAAGGAGAGGUUAAAUGAGAGAAAAGGCUUUGUGCUGGGAAGAAUGGAGAUAAAAAUAUGUUGGUUCCAUGUUAAUAGAAUGGUGGAGUCCAGUUUGUCCAGAAUUAUCCUUGAAUCAGAGUGUCUCUAUACAGUGUAAAACAUAUCAGAGAAGUUUAUGACUUUAAAGAAAAUUUCAUAAAAAUACAUGACCCCCUAAAGGAGUUUACAUGCAGAACUAUUUUGGGGAAAAUUUAUGAGUAGUCAUUCAGUAUAUAACGAGCUUUAUUCAGCAUUGUAAUUUUCCAGUUUGUGUAUGAUGAAUUCAUAGAGCUCAUUAAGUGUAAGUGUCAUUGUUGUGAUUCAUUCAAGCCUUUUUCCUCUCUUCAGCAGAAGGUUAAAAAAAAAUUCCAAAUUUGAAUCCAGGACUUGAAGAAUGCCAGUUGUCUAAAUACAGUACCAUAUUGUGAUAAAUAUAGCUAUUGAAAUUUUUAAAAAUCUAUUCACAAAACUUUAUUUUAAUAUUCAUAGCAGAACUUUUUUUGGAAUGUUAUCUGAAAAACAGAGGACCAUUUUAUCAUCAGAGCUGACUAUUAAUUAGGGUAUUGUUGCAGAUAUAAAAGUUGAUCUGCCACUGAAAUUCUAUUUGAAUAUGUAUAGUUCCAAGCUUGCUUUGUGUAUUUAAUAACUUUAGUACCAUAAUUACUCUGUUUACAAUUAAAUUUUGGUGAAUAUGCUAAUAUGGAAUAUACCAAUGAGUGAUUUCAGCAAAGGGCAGUAUUGAUUUGCAUCUUGAUGUGCUUUUCAGUUGCAUCUGCAUUUCAUUUAAUAUCAGAGGAAAAGAAGUGGUCAGAUUAUGUAAUGCUAAACUUUUUUUUCUUUGAAACCUCUCUGUUGCAUUGGCUACUAUAAAAGUAGACUUGCAUAGAGUCAGAGGGGCUGAAAUUAUGUGGAAAGAUUUAAUUUUGUUAAAGUUUGUGCCUUUCGGUAUAUUCAUUAAUAGAAACCUUAAUGCAAGCAUCGGUUUCAUUAUUAGAAGAAACCUAUAAUGUACUAAAGUGAUUGUUUAAUUCUAAUUAGUAUUUUAAGUUCUUCAGAAAACUCACUAACUUACUGAAGCAAAUACUUGUGAUUAUUUUAUUUCUUUGAGCAGGGACUUCUGGUUUUAAAUAAUUCCUCUUUUAAGAAAUUGCCUGAAAAGCAACAAGGAGAUUGAGAAACAGUGAUUUCAUAUUCUGAGAAACUGAGAAGCUUCUGUAGCCCUGAACUAGAAAAUAAGGAGCUGCCAAAUUCAGUGAAGGUCAAACAGGGUAUGGGAGGAUGCUGAAAGGGAACCUGAGACACAGAUGUCAGGAAAGCUGGCAGAACUGUGUUCUCUAAAGAAAGGGGCACACCCUGAGAGGCACAUUAAUAAGCCUUUGUCUGGGAGAACAGGAAUAGGUGUUGGCAGGCAGGGGCACUAGGGAACUUUAUGGUGUGAUGAAAAUGUUCUGUCUGGUGGUCGCACAAGUGUAUGUACGUUUGUAAAAUUUUGUCAGUUUACUUUGUGCAAGUUAGUAAUUUAUUGCCUCUCAACUCCAAAUUCACCCCUUUUUGCUCUAUUUAUAUACUCGAGCCAGACCUUUUAAAUAUUUUUUCUUUUCCUGGACAGUGUUAGAUUUUGUCAGUAGAAGGUGAGGAAGGGAUACUGCAAGACUUAGCAGAGAAAGUGCUUCUCUUGUUGCCAUGUGCUUGUUUUUUUGUUCGUUUGUUUGUUUUUCUUAAUCUCUUAAGGUGUGGCUGUCAGCUCUACUUACUCUCCUGUAAGCUUCAUUAGCACCCUGGUAGGCAGCUUCUUGCUCCCACCAGUAUCUCGUGGGCAGCAGAUUCCUGUGGAUAAGCUGUAGCUCACUGGCCCUACAGAGAACUACCCUACCGCUCAGUGGGUCACUGCCACAGUCUGUCCAGUGAAGUGUUCCUUUCUUGGGCACUCUCCCUUAGCCUUGGAGACAGUAACUGCUCCCUAUAUUUGCUAGUUCCAUAUUCCUUCAAAUUGUCUUUUACAUCUAUUAGCACUUGACAACUUUUUACAAAUUAAUAAUUUUUUAUUUAUGUUACAUUUUCUUGUUUUAAUUGAUUGUUUGUUUUCUAGCUCCUGAAUGGACACUGACUGUUAUCACACACUUGUGAUUUGUGUACCUUACUUACUGUGUUAAUUUUACAUAAAUAAACAGGAUGAAAUAAUAAGUAUACUUCUUGAUUACUUUCUAUAACAUGAACCAAUUGUUUAAACACCAAGAUUGGGAUAUAGAAUGCUACCAGAUCCCUAGGAACCAUCCACCUCCAGCCAUUUCUUCUGACCCUUAGUCCCCAAAGUGAUAUCUGCUGUUUGACUUGUAUCACCAUUGAUUUGUUUUAUUAUUGAAAUUCAUGUAAAUGGAAUAUAGUAUGUACUCUUCUGUCUGGUGCUGCUUUUUCUUAACACAGUGUUUGGUAUGUCCAUCCGUCUUACUAUAUUCAUUUUCCUGUUGUUGGACAUACAGGUUUCCAGUUUGUGGCUGUUGUGAAUAAAGCUGUUAUCAUUCUUGUACAUGUCUUUGGGUGGACAUGUACAUGCAUAGAAGUUGAAUUGCUGGGUCGGUUAGCAGGUACUGCCAAAUGAAUUUUCAAAAUGAUCGAAACAGUAUACAGUGUAGGAGAGUUCUGUUUGUUCCAACUCCUUACCAACACUUUGUAGUGUCAGACUUUUGCAGUUGAAGUCUUCAAAACCUUAAGGAAUAGAUCAAAUGCUGCUUAAACUCCUUAGAUUGUGGUAAAGGAAGAAAAGCUUCCAAAAUCUUAUUAUGAAGUGAGCAUAAUAUUGAUACUUAAACAGAUAAAUGUAGCAGAAAAAAUAAACUACAGACCAUUCUUAUGAAUAUCAGUCUUGUCUAUGGCUAUACCACCCUGAGUGUGCCCGAUCUCGUCUAAAUAUCAGUCUUGUUCCUAAAUAAAAUAUUAGCAAAUAGAAUUCAGCAGCACACUAAAAAAAUUAUAACUGCCACCAAGUAUAAUUUUUUUUUUUCUAGGAAGGUUGUGUUAAAUAGCUCUAUAUGAGUAUGUGGUAUACCAGCUGUAUUUAAGUCUUUUGUGUUUCUCAAGAUGCUAAAAGAUAAGUAUUGAACAAGUAUUUAUUAGUACACUGCCAUUGGCCCUGCUUAUACCUGGCUGAAGCAGGCCCUAAGGAUUGACAGGGCCUUUGGUUGCCUGAGGCCACCUGAGAUUAUAGGGGCCAGCAAGAGCAAGAGGGAAUCCUCCACAUCUUUUUCCAUUAGAAGCCACAGGAGGGAGUUUCAUUUAGAUACAUUUUAAAGAAAUAUUUCUGUCAUAGUGGCCUCUUGCAGAGCAGCUGAGUAUAUUUCAGUGACUUCUUAACGUUUAUGCGCAAGACACAGAGCUACUCUGUUUAAUAUACAACAUAUAAGAUGUGCCUGGAAAUAAAAAGCAAGACUAAUAAUUCAAAAGAAAAAUGAGCCGAGGUUACUCAUAGUUUACAGGAAAUAAAGUACAGAUUUUGCUUAGGAGUGUUUUCUUUUAAUUUUUUUUUUUUUUUUUGAGAGGGAAGUGGGAAUGGACUGGGCAUGCUCAUUGAGUAUGAGAGGAUUUCCAGUUUUGAUCCCUUGGUGAAUAUUAAUUAUAGGAGCAAUAAUCAUUUUGUUAAGGAACCUGGUUUCUUUUCAUGGGAAGUGGUAUUUUAAGACUACAAUUUGUUUGCUAGGGAUGCUCUUUGCUGCUGGGUUGAUUAUUGUUUCUAAGCUUUUUAGUGAAUGGGGCUAGGAAAUACAAAGAUGUGUUUCUGUGUAUGUGUUUAUUUUAAAGAUACAUUCUGAACUAAAAAUAUUUCCAAGUACAGCAUUUUUACCUUUACCUAUUCUAUCUUUUAUCUCUGUCUCUUUCUUCCAUAUCUGAAUCCUGAUGUUCAGGGACACAAGAGAAUGAUAGAAUAAUAAUAUCACAUAAUUACUCAUUUGCAUCAUUCCACAUGUAUGCACACAACAGUCUUAGUUAACAAAAUCAAGUAUCACAAUAUGAUUUCUGGAAAGUUGCCUUUUUUGCGUAUGUUAUCCCAUUUUUUGAUAGUUGUACUAUAUCUACAGUGUCAGUACAUUUGCCCAUUAUAUACUCUUUUCUCUCUUUUAUAACCCUUGUUGAGUCUCAGUUCUACAAGUAUAUAUUUACUGCUCACUGAUAUUGACAUUUCUUUAGUCAUUUUGGAUAUUGCUAUGGGAGUGGCAGACCCCUUCUACUGGGCUUCUUCUCUAGUAGAUUCUUAUUGCUGUUUUCUAUAUUGAUAACACUUAGCAGUCUUUAUACUCGAAAUUUAGCUGGGUAUAAAAUCUUUGGUUCAUGUUUCCUUUCUUAGAGUCUUAAAUAUGUUACUUUUUUUCCCCUGGCAUAAAAUGUUGCUGUUAAAGUGAUGACAAUUUGAUUUUAUUUUCCUUAUAAAAUAUCUGCAGAUGCUCAAAAAGUAUUUUCAUUUACUAUUAAGUUAACUAAAUUAUAUCUUGGUGAUGGUCAUUCUGGGUUGAUUUUUCAAAUGUAUGUGAUAUGACCUUUCAAAAUGUAGUUUUAUGUUUAAAUGAAGUUCAGGAAAGUUUUCUUGAAUUAAAUGAUUUUUAAUAUUCUGUUCCCUUGCUUUGAUUUUCUUUGUUAUAUGUAUGUUGGUUUUUUUGUGUAUGUUUUCUUAAACAUUUUUUGGUCCUUUUUGAUUUUUUUGUUUUUUUCCUUUUCACUUUCUAUUUCUCUUGUCAUUAAAAAGUUUUAUUUACUCUUAUGUUCCUUCUCAUGUAGUUUUUAUUUCCGAACUGAUUUUUGUCUUUCAUUUUCAAUUAUUCUGUCAUCUGAUUUCUGAAUUUUUCUAAUUCUGAUUGAUGUUAGUCUGUACAUAAAGUGUUUUUUAGCUUGUUUUGAAAUACUAAUUUAUAGCUAUCAACCUUUUGGGAGGCAUGUUUUCUUAUGUACUUUUCUAAAGGGAUUUUUUUUCUCUUUAAAAAUACCAACUUAGUGUGGCACUAGGCUUUGAUCCAUUUUUGUUGCUGAGUUUCGUAUGCAGCCAGUUUUCCCUUAUAUGCAAUUAGUUUUAGAUAGUCUGGUUCAGGGUGAGUGUAUGUCAUUCUCUAGAUCCCACUCUUCACUUGUUUUUGUGUAGUAUUCCAAAAUACUGAGGCUAACUUAUAGAUCCACUUUCAUUUGAACUUUCUUUUUCCUUUCUUCGUAUUAUCCUUGUGAUGUUCACUUUGGCUUCAUCCCUAGCAGUUUCUCCUCAGCCUGAGGCUUUGACCUAGAAGGGGCUUUGGCUGGUUAGUUUUGAGAGUUGUAGAGGCAACAGGCUUCAGCCUCUUGAGACCUCACCAAGGACCCCUUGCACUUCCUGGCUGUGGGAGUGGCAGAGCCCUUCUUCUUUCAGUUGCUUUUCUCACAGUGUCUUGUGUGCUUCUAAGAAGUAGCUCCUGAUAAUUUUUGGAUCCUAAGAUUUAUCAGAGGCACCAUACUUUCUUCUGCUUCCUUCUUUACAGUUGCUGAUACCACACAGAUCUUACUGCUGUUUGUCAUGGUCUGUCUUCACCUGCUCAAAUUUUGUAGAGAUAAAGGGAUACUGUCCCUCCGUUUGGUUGGAGAGGUUGUCCAUAGGUGUUGAGUUUUGCUAUCCAGUUGUCCUGUCCAGUUUUAUGGGGGAAUUCAGGGAGAUGAAACAGCUGUGCUGCUGCCUCCACCAUGUCCAGCGUUAACCUUCAGGAGCUGUGAUUUAGAAGCAUAUUGAAGAUACUGACAGCGAUGACGCUGUUCUGUGGGACUAUUUUUAGGAAAGAAAGUCAUUCCAAGCCUUAAUUAAUUAUUACAAUUAGUUUCAAUUAGUUGGCCACAGAAAUAAAACUAAAAAUAAAAGCAAACAGCUUUAUUUGGAGGAAAAUCACUUUUUAUUGACCACAAUUUACAUUGAAUAGAUGCUGAGCCAGAAUAUUUCAUUUAAAAUAUAUUUUUGUCACUUCUGGAAAGGAAUUUCAGAAAAACACAAAAGAUUGUCCAGUCACUAUUUUGAGAUAUAUAAAGAUAAAAAACAUGUUGUCCACUCAUUUUAAACUAUUUUGAUUACUAUAAGGAACCAGUCAAAUAAGAGAUUACUCUGAUGAUUUGAUAAAGUGGGUUGAAAUUCAGAAGGGCAUCUGUUUUAAUAUUUGGAAGUACUAUGUGUUUUAGUUGUUUCUUUUAUUUGGUUUACUACCAUAGGUGUAAAAGUAACCUUUCUUGGUGUUUUGAGUCUAGGCUAGCUUGGUUGGCACAGAAAUUCCAUUUUGCAAGAUUUUACCAUGAGUAAAAACACAUUAAUUAAGAGAACUAAUUGACAUGAAGAAAUAAGAGACACUUUUAUUUAUUUUGAAGAUGUUUUUGUUAACUUAGAGAAGAUUUAGACAGCGAAGAUGCAUUAGUAUUCUAUAGGAAAAAAUUCAAUUUAAAAAGUCCCCAGUAAAUUAAUAAGGAACAUUUUCAGAUAAGGAGUUUGUGUAUUUGGAGUGAUAGUGGGUGAGUUGGUGAAAAAUUCCAGUUGAAUCUAGUGUGUAUGUAUGUAGCAUGUCUAGGCUCAAAACUGAGCUCAAAACUGAGCUACAGACUUCUUUCAUCUGAAUAGCCAUUUCAAGUGUUGCAUACUGUCUUAAUCAUUCUUAUUAACCUUCUUUCUUUUCUAUAUCUCCAGUAUGUUUUUAGGGAACUGUGGAACCUAACAAAUACUUAUUUUAAAUCUUUUUUGAUUAACAUUUAUAGAACCGAGAGUUUGAAAUCACACAACAAACACAUGUUCACAUGCAUACUAGUACAAAUUGAGUUCCUUCAGUCAACGAAGUGAGUUACACCUGAGGGCACUUGAAGCCCAGUGUGAAGUGACUUGAUCAAGAUUACCCAACCAGCUGGUGUCAUACCUGCAAUCCAGGUCUUUUGAUUCCAUGAAAAUGCCUCGUGUAAAAGCAGCUCAAGCUGGAAGACAGAGCUCUGCAAAGAGACAUCUUGCAGAACAAUUUGCAGUUGGAGAGAUAAUAACUGACAUGGCAAAAAAGGAAUGGAAAGUAGGAUUACCCAUUGGCCAAGGAGGCUUUGGCUGUAUAUAUCUUGCUGAUAUGAAUUCUUCAGAGUCAGUUGGCAGUGAUGCACCUUGUGUUGUAAAAGUGGAACCCAGUGACAAUGGACCUCUUUUUACUGAAUUAAAGUUCUACCAACGAGCUGCAAAACCAGAGCAAAUUCAGAAAUGGAUUCGUACCCGUAAGCUGAAGUACCUGGGUGUUCCUAAGUAUUGGGGGUCUGGUCUACAUGACAAAAAUGGAAAAAGUUACAGGUUUAUGAUAAUGGAUCGCUUUGGGAGUGACCUUCAGAAAAUAUAUGAAGCAAAUGCCAAAAGGUUUUCUCGGAAAACUGUCUUGCAGCUAAGCUUAAGAAUUCUGGAUAUUCUGGAAUAUAUUCACGAGCAUGAGUAUGUGCAUGGAGAUAUCAAGGCCUCAAAUCUUCUUCUGAACUACAAGAAUCCUGACCAGGUGUACUUGGUAGAUUAUGGCCUUGCUUAUCGGUACUGCCCAGAAGGAGUUCAUAAAGAAUACAAAGAAGACCCCAAAAGAUGUCACGAUGGCACUAUUGAAUUCACGAGCAUCGAUGCACACAAUGGCGUGGCCCCAUCAAGACGUGGUGAUUUGGAAAUACUUGGUUAUUGCAUGAUCCAAUGGCUUACUGGCCAUCUUCCUUGGGAGGAUAAUUUGAAAGAUCCUAAAUAUGUUAGAGAUUCCAAAAUUAGAUACAGAGAAAAUAUUGCAAGUUUGAUGGACAAAUGUUUUCCUGAGAAAAACAAACCAGGUGAAAUUGCCAAAUACAUGGAAACAGUGAAAUUACUAGACUACACUGAAAAACCUCUUUAUGAAAAUUUACGUGACAUUCUUUUGCAAGGACUAAAAGCUAUAGGAAGUAAGGAUGAUGGCAAAUUGGACCUCAGUGUUGUGGAGAAUGGAGGUUUGAAAGCAAAAACAAUAACAAAGAAGCGAAAGAAAGAAAUUGAAGAAAGCAAGGAACCUGGUGUUGAAGAUACGGAAUGGUCAAACACACAGACAGAGGAGGCCAUACAGACCCGAAGUGAGGAGUCCCAAGGAGCAAUACAUCGAAGCAUGUCUCAGCCAGAGGCUAGCAGCAGCAGCUAUGACAGUUCAAGAACCAGAAAGAGAGUCCAGAAGUAAUUCAGAUGCUGUGAACCAGAUUUCCUUUUCUUUGUUUUCUUUUGACUUUUUUCUCCUUUUCUAUUUGAACUGUUUUAUUUUCCUGUGAGUCUUGCGAGGUGGAAGUAAUGAUUAAAUACUCAUGUGUUCAGAAAACAUAAACUUUUUUUAUAAAAAUAUUUUGUACAAUUCAUUAAAGGCUAAUUUAUGAAAUUUGAAAAUCUUCAGGUUAUACUCCUUAAGUUAUCCCAAAGCCGUGUGUUUGUGAUGUUUUGGAGUACAUAUAUAUGAAAAUUAUUAUGACACGCACUUUUCUAAUCAUUGUACAUUUCUCAGAGUGGAUAAAAAUGUUUGACAAAGUCCUCACUUUUAAGGAAAUGCAAAGCUUAAAAUAAAACUCUCUUUUGUUUGAUGCAAACACA